GGAUGUUCGUUGGGGAUUCAACAUGGCGGCGGGAGUGUCCGCGGUGGUGGCGGUGCAAGAGAGCUGAGGGAGGCGCGAGGGCGCGGAGUUCCAGGUCGAGCAGUUAGGCCGCGAGCGACUGCGGCGCCGAGCCGAUGAGUAACCCGAAGCCCCUAGAGGAGUGGUCACCUGCCUGAGGGCACUUCUGUCCCACCAGCAUCAGACCAGGUGUGUGCAGGCUCUCUAUGGGAUGCCGCCAUCAGAAUGUCUCUUCCUCAGCCCCUUUGUUUUUUAAAGUGGCUUUGGUCGACCAUUUGCUCUGUGCUUGGUACUGUGUCAAGGGCCCGAUUGAAGACCACAGAUCCUAAAGAUAGGGGAGUGUCGCGACAAGGCUGCCUGGGGUGCCCUCUUAACCCAGGGGAUCAGUAACCCUGUGCUGAGUCAAUAUCCAAAGGCCGCACCGAGUCCCCGGCACCAUGUUUGGGAAGAGGAAGAAGCGGGUGGAGAUCUCCGCGCCGUCCAACUUCGAGCACCGCGUGCACACGGGCUUCGACCAGCACGAGCAGAAGUUCACGGGGCUGCCCCGCCAGUGGCAGAGCCUGAUCGAGGAGUCGGCUCGCCGGCCCAAGCCCCUCGUCGACCCCGCCUGCAUCACCUCCAUCCAGCCCGGGGCCCCCAAGACCAUCGUGCGGGGCAGCAAAGGUGCCAAAGAUGGGGCCCUCACGCUGCUGCUGGACGAGUUUGAGAACAUGUCGGUGACACGCUCCAACUCCCUGCGGAGAGACAGCCCGCCGCCGCCCGCCCGUGCCCGCCAGGAAAAUGGGAUGCCAGAGGAGCCGGCCACCACGGCCAGAGGGGGCCCAGGGAAGGCAGGCAGCCGAGGCCGGUUCGCCGGUCACAGCGAGGCGGGUGGCGGCAGUGGUGACAGGCGACGGGCGGGGCCAGAGAAGAGGCCCAAGUCUUCCAGGGAGGGCUCAGGGGGUCCCCAGGAGUCCUCCCGGGACAAACGCCCCCUCUCCGGGCCUGAUGUCGGCACCCCCCAGCCUGCUGGUCUGGCCAGUGGGGCGAAACUGGCAGCUGGCCGGCCCUUUAACACCUACCCGAGGGCUGACACGGACCACCCAUCCCGGGGUGCCCAGGGGGAGCCUCAUGACGUGGCCCCUAACGGGCCAUCAGCGGGGGGCCUGGCCAUCCCCCAGUCCUCCUCCUCCUCCUCCCGGCCUCCCACCCGAGCCCGAGGUGCCCCCAGCCCUGGAGUGCUGGGACCCCACGCCUCAGAGCCCCAGCUGGCCCCUCCAGCCUGCACCCCCGCCGCCCCUGCUGUUCCUGGGCCCCCUGGCCCCCGCUCACCACAGCGGGAGCCACAGCGAGUAUCCCAUGAGCAGUUCCGGGCUGCCCUGCAGCUGGUGGUGGACCCAGGCGACCCCCGCUCCUACCUGGACAACUUCAUCAAGAUUGGCGAGGGCUCCACGGGCAUCGUGUGCAUCGCCACCGUGCGCAGCUCGGGCAAGCUGGUGGCCGUCAAGAAGAUGGACCUGCGCAAGCAGCAGAGGCGCGAGCUGCUCUUCAACGAGGUGGUAAUCAUGAGGGACUACCAGCACGAGAAUGUGGUGGAGAUGUACAACAGCUACCUGGUGGGGGACGAGCUCUGGGUGGUCAUGGAGUUCCUGGAAGGAGGCGCCCUCACCGACAUCGUCACCCACACCAGGAUGAACGAGGAGCAGAUCGCGGCCGUGUGCCUUGCAGUGCUGCAGGCCCUGUCGGUGCUCCACGCCCAGGGCGUCAUCCACCGGGACAUCAAGAGCGACUCGAUCCUGCUGACCCAUGAUGGCAGGGUGAAGCUGUCAGACUUUGGGUUCUGCGCCCAGGUGAGCAAGGAAGUGCCCCGAAGGAAGUCGCUGGUCGGCACGCCCUACUGGAUGGCCCCAGAGCUCAUCUCCCGCCUUCCCUACGGGCCAGAGGUAGACAUCUGGUCGCUGGGGAUAAUGGUGAUUGAGAUGGUGGACGGAGAGCCCCCCUACUUCAACGAGCCACCCCUCAAAGCCAUGAAGAUGAUUCGGGACAACCUGCCACCCCGACUGAAGAACCUGCACAAGGUGUCGCCAUCCCUGAAGGGCUUCCUGGACCGCCUGCUGGUGCGAGACCCUGCCCAGCGGGCCACGGCAGCCGAGCUGCUGAAGCACCCAUUCCUGGCCAAGGCAGGGCCGCCUGCCAGCAUCGUGCCCCUCAUGCGCCAGAACCGCACCAGAUGAGGCCCAGCGCCCUUCCCCUCAACCAAAGAGCCCCCCGGGUCACCCCCGCCCCACUGAGGCCAGUAGGGGGCCAGGCCUCCCACUCCUCCCAGCCCGGGAGAUGCUCCGCGUGGCACCACCCUCCUUGCUGGGGGUAGAUGAGACCCUACUACUGAACUCCAGUUUUGAUCUCGUGACUUUUAGAAAAACACAGGGACUCGUGGGAGCAAGCGAGGCUCCCAGGACCCCCACCCUCUGGGACAGGCCCUCCCCCAUGUUCUUCUGUCUCCAGGAAGGGCAGCGGCCCUCCCAUCACUGGAAGUCUGCAGUGGGGGUCGCUGGGGGUGGAGAGAACACUAAGAGGUGAACAUGUAUGAGUGUGUGCACGCGUGUGAGUGUGCAUGUGUGUGUGUGCAAAGGUCCAGCCACCCCGUCCUCCAGCCUGCAAGGGGUGUCUGGCGCCUUGCCUGACACCCAGCCCCCUCUCCCCCUGAGCCAUUGUGGGGGUCGAUCAUGAAUGUCCGAAGAGUGGCCUUUUCCCGUAGCCCUGCGCCCCCUUUCUGUGGCUGGAUGGGGAGACAGGUCAGGGCCCCCCACCCUCUCCAGCCCCUGCAGCAAAUGACUACUGCACCUGGACAGCCUCCUCUUUUCUAGAAGUCUAUUUAUAUUGUCAUUUUAUAACACUCUAGCCCCUGCCCUUAUUGGGGGACAGAUGGUCCCUGUCCUGCGGGGUGGCCCUGGCAGAACCACUGCCUGAAGAACCAGGUUCCUGCCCGGUCAGCGCAGCCCCAGCCCGCCCACCCCUGCCUCGAGUUAGUUUUACAAUUAAAACAUUGUCUUGUUUUGUGUCUGUGUGCGAUGUGUGGGGGGCAGGGGGCCCUGCCCGGCUGUCUUGGGUGGGAAUUUGCAGGGAGAGGGUCUGGAUCUGGGAGCAAACCACGAUUCCAGCCAAGGCAGGGCAAGGGUGGGGUGGGGAGUGGGGAGUUCAGGUCAUAGCAGCCAGUAAGCUCCCCCAGCCUGCCACUCCCCAGAAUGGGGCAGGAUUGUCCCCACCCCUGGAAGCAGCCAGUUUGCCACAGUCCAUGUGCAGACUGAUCCCAGUUUGCCAAAUCUGCAAUUUCCUGGAACCUUUUAAAGGCUGUCUUGAGCGCGUUUGGUGAGUAGGAGCUAACCCAAGUUAGUAAAUUGAAGGCCAUUUGGCAAAUUGGUCAGUGGGCAGAUGGGCUUUUGGGGAUUGACUGAGGCUGACUGGCCUGGAGCUGCUGGCUUCGGAGAGACACCCUGUGAAGUGUGUCCUUCCACGCAGGAGCCCAGAGCCGAGCCCACGCUGGGGGGAAUCUGACUGGCAUGGAGGUGGCCAUGCCACCAUCGCUGCUGCAGCUGCAUCCUGGCACUUUGCGCCUCAGGCCCUGUUGGGCUCCACUUUCUGCAUCCUCCCCAGCCCCCAGGGAGGCAGUGGAGUGGGGAGAGAGCCAGGAGUGAGCCUCCGUCCCCAAAGCCAGCCAGGCGUCAUCAGCACCAGAGACCUCAGCCUGGUCCUCUCGGGAAGUGAGUGGCCAGGGCAGAGAUUCCAGGUUAGUCCACGCCUCCCACCCUUCACAGGUCCUGACCCCAAGAAUCAGAGCACUGUGUGUGUGGCAGGGCCUAUGCCAAGUGCAAACACAGCCUAGAUGGAUCAUCACAGAGUGAAACCCAGCGGUGCAAGCAGCUGUGCUCUCUGCGAUGUAUUGGAGGCUUAGGUGAGGUGGAUGCCUUUCUGGAAAAAAAAAAAAUGCUAACAUUGGCAAAAGAAGAAAUAGAAAACAAGACCAAAAUAACUGUCUCCUCACUGCACACACACUCCAGAAUAAAUAAAAGGUUUCAGGCUUGAAUGCACUUUCAAAUGAGAUUUUUUUUUUUUUUUUGAGACGGAGUAUCGCUCUGUCGCCCAGGCUGGAGUGCAGUGGCACGAUCUUGGCUCACUGCAACUUCUGCCUCCUGGGUUCAAGCGAUUCUCCUGCCUCAGCCUCCCAAGUAGCUGGGAUUACAGGCGCUUGCCACCACGCCAGGCUAAUUUUUUGUAUUUUGAGUAGAGACUGGAUUUCGCCAUCUUGGCCAGACUGGUCUUGAACUCCUGACCUCGUGAUCCACCCACCUCAGCCUCCCAAAGUGCUGGGAUUACAGGCAUGAGCCACCAUGCCUGGCCUCAAAUGAGGUUUACCAGACUUUGAAGGAGCAGGUAAUUCCUUCUACCUUGUGAACAAGUUGUUCCAGAAAGAUAGCAGCUCAGGAGGCCUCUGUGACCAUGGUUCCAGACCCAGAUAAGGACGGCAAAGAACAGAGCAUCUCAGAAACGCAAGGCUCACAGCCAGGGUGCCCGGCGACCCCACGGGCACUGAGAACAGCUAGCUCUAGGAGCUCCACUCUCCUGCUGAAGAAACCACGGGCUCAGAGACGGGGAGCUCCCUCGCCCAGCCACAUCUGUGACCCCACGGUAACUCUGCUGGUUUUGGUGCCUUCAGUCACUCACUGCAGGUUUGUUUUGUUUUGUUUUGUUUUGAGUUUUUUUGUUUUUUGUUUUUUGUUUUUAGAGACAAGAUGUUGCUAUGUUGCCUAGGCUGGUUUCGAACUCCUGGCCUCAAGGGAUCCUCCCUCCUUGGCCCCGCAAAGUGCUGGGAUUACAGGCGUGAGCCACCGUGCCCAGCCCGCUCACUGCAGUUUGAAGGCAUGGCUUUGGGUGGCGUGGGGUGAAAGCUGCCCGAGGCCCCGUUCCUCCCCACGUGGCUGCCUCCUGCCAGAGCCAGUCAGGAAAACAGACCCCAACUAGAGUUGUUUCAAAUGGCAGGGAUUUGGUACCGGUGGUUGGAUCAUGACAAAGCUCUGAGAAGGCUGGAGGAGCCACAGAGUGCCAAGUGCCCAGCAAUCAUUAGAGGAAGGAGGCUGCUGCCACCUGUGUGGCUAGAGGAACAGAGGGGCCAAUGGCAUUCCCCAAACCCCACUCUCGCCUCUGUCUGGCCAGAGCAGAAUGGCUUCUUCCAGCUUCCCACCCUGGACUCCCACCCAGGAGCCUCCUCCUGGCAGACCCUUCCUGACCCCACCGGCCCGGGGGGUCUACAGAUCCAUGUUUCAGGCGUCCGCCUGGAGCGGAACAGGGGAGUGCUUAGGACAAGGGUGGUGCCAGAGGAUCCACUCUGCCCACAUUUAGUUGACCAGCUGAGGCACUCCACGGGAAUGAAUGACUCUCGACAGGUGCCGGAGGUGAGGAGGGGCCCGGAGGCCCAGGAGGGGCACAGGGAUGGAUUCGUCCGCCUGGGGGCUGGAGGUGUGUUUACAGAGCCCCAAAAUAAACAAUGCAACCAGGUCAGACCAGCGGUUCUCACAGUGUGGUUCCCAGACCAGCAGCAUCACUGGGAGCUUACUGGACACGCAAAUAAAUCCCUGUGUGCCACCCCAGCUGCAUCAGAUGCUGGUGGGGCCCAGUGAUCUGUAUUUAACACACCCUCCGGGGGAUGCCGGUGCCCACUCACGUUUGAGAACCCCUGCGAUCCACGACUGCCCUCCCGUGUAAAAGGCCCACCUCUGUGGGACUCCAAGUCAUCAGCACCCUAGGGUCCUUCCGUCUUUUUCCUUCCUCCUGGGACACCUGCCUCUCCCAUGUCGUAUUAGAGAAUUCCUUAUGCUCCCAAGUGGGCACGGGGAGAGGAAGGCACUCCUCUUUAAGGACCGACCCAGAGGUUUUGCCAUUGCUUCACUGGCCAGAGCUUAGUCACGCAGCCUCACCCAGAGGCAAGGGAGGUUGGAAAAUGUAGUGUUUGUGUGUGUCUAACACAAAUUCUAUUACCAUGCAGUCAGGAUUCUCCACUCUUGCUCUUUCAUUAGAUUUGCUGGGCUUCACCCUGGACUUUCUGAUUUAGUGACAGAACAGAGAACCCAGAGGCAGACCCAGAUGUGUACAAGGGCUUCAUAUACAAUCAGGAGAUUUAAUAAUCAUGCUAGGGGCCGGGUGCAGUGGCUCACGCCUGUAAUCCCAAGCACUUUGGGGAGCCGAGGCAGGCAGAUCACUUGAGGUCAGGAGUUUGAGACCAGCCUGGGCAACAAAGUGAGACCCUGUCUCUACUAAAAAUAACAAAAAUUAGCCGGGCGUGGUGGUGGGCGCCUGUAAUCCCAGCUCCUCGGGUGGCUGAGGCAUGAGAAUCACUUGAACCCAGGAGGCAGAGGUUUCAGUGAGCUGAGAUCACAUCACUGCACUCCAGCCUGGGUGACAGAGUGAGAUUCUGUC